GCCAGGCUAGUCUCAAAGUCCUGACCUCAAGUGAUUCACCUGCCUAGGCCUCUCAAUGUGCUGGGAUUAUAGGCAACUGCGCCAGGCCAGCUUCCUUACUUGUAACAUUGGAUAAAAUGUCUUGAUAUCUGUCUGGUAGAAAUACUUCAGAAGCAAUGAUCUGGUUGGUGGCCAAGGGUGGGGACACAGAUGAAGCAUGACUGGCCACACAUCAUUAACCUUUGCCAAGCUGGGCGAUGGGCACGUGAGAUCAUUCUUUUUUUAACUGAGACAGGGUUUUACUCUGUCGCCCAGGCUGGAGUGCAGUGGCGCAAUAUUGGCUCACUGCAACCUCUGCCUCCUGGGCUCAAGCAAUCCUCCUACUUCAGCCUUCUAAGUAGCUGGGACUACAGGCAUGCACCACCAUGCCUGGCUAAUUUUUGUAUUUUUAGUAGAGACAGGGUUUCACUAUGUUGGCCAGGCUGACAUUUUUUUUUUCUUUUCCUUUUUUUUUUUUGAGACAGAGUCUUGCUCAGUCUUGCCCAGGCUGGAGUGCAAUGGUGCAAUCAUGGCUCACUGCAGCCUCAACUUCCCGGGCUCAAGCAAUUCUCCCACCUCAGCCUCCCGAGUAGCUGGCACUACAGGCAUGCACCACCAUGCCCAGCUAUUUUUUAAUUUUUUGUGGAGAUGGGCUAACACUAUGCUGUUGCCCUGGCUGGUCUCGAACUCCCAGGCUCAGGUGGUCCUCCCACCUUGACCUCCCAAAGUGCUGGGAUUACGGGUGUGAGCCACUGUGUCUGGCCCUGUACCUGACAUUUUCCAUGAUAAAAAGUUAAAAUAAAAAUGAGACAGGCUAUAAAAAUGACAUUUCACAGGUCACUAGUGAAAAUGGCAUGUGGGUAUUAAGGGCUUCGCACGGAGCCUGUGGGAAGGGCUCCUUUCCUUGCAAGGAGUAAGGUGUGGUUUCUCCCUUUUACAGGUCAGGAAACCACUGUUCCCCACAGACUUAGGUACUUGCCCAAGGUCAUGUAGUAGUUAGUGAGGGAGCCAGGCUUUAUUUAUUUAUUUACUUGAGAGACGGUGUCUUGCUCUGUCACUCAGGCUGGAGUGCAGUGGCACAAUCACAGUCCACUGCAGCCUUGUACUCCUGGACUCAAGGGAUCUUUCCACCCCAGCCUUCUGAGCAGCUGGGACUACAGGUGCACACCACCACACCUGGCUAAUUUUUUAAAUUUUUUGUAGGGAUGGAGUAUCCCUAUGUUGCCCAGGCUAGUCUCAAACUCCUGGCCUCAAGUGAUCCUCCUUUGUCAGCCAUAAGAGCCACCUUACCCGGUCUGAGAGCCAGGCUUUAAAUGUAGUUCCAGCUGCUUUGAAGCCCAGCUCUCACAUUCCAGCUGUACUUCCUCUUAAGGGACAUUGCCAGAGCUAAGGUCAGUCUUUGAUUCAUGGGCAGACAUCCCCUCCACAGAUGCUGCUGGGGUGUGUAGCAGUACCAUGGGGGACAGCUAAGCGUUGGCUCCUGGCAGCAGGAGGAAUGAGGUCACUUGGGAGAGGGGGUGACAUCAGGGUGGACUCACCCCACACCACUGCUCGGGAGACCUGUAUUUCCAGCAGUAACUCCCAGGGCCUCCUUUUGAAAUGCUGGUUCAAAUCCGGGCUCAGUAGCUUAUGCCUGUAAUCCCAGCACUUUGGGAGGCUGAGGCAGGCAGAUCACUUGAGGUCAGGAGUUCGAGACCAGCCUGGCCAACAUGGCGAAACCCCAUCUCUACUAAAAAUACAAAAAUUAUUUGGGCAUGGUGGUGCACGCCUAUAGUCUGGCUGCUCGGGAGCCUGAGGCAGUAGAAUCGCUUGAACCCAGGAGGCGAAGGUUGCAGUGAGCUGAGAUUGCGCCACUGCACUCCAGCCUGGGCGACAGAGGAGACGAUCUCCAAAACAAAACAAAGAAAUGCUGGUUCGGGAGGCACACAGCCCUAGACUUUUGGGCUAUAUCCUUGGCAGUGACUGUUGAUCAGCUUCUGGUUGUUUCAAGGACACCUGUAAGACUGGAGACCCAGUUGAGCCAAGAGUGGGGCACAUCAGGAAGACUAGGGGAUGGAAAAGCACUGGUCCCCCUGGGCUGCUGGCUCUCUUCUUGCUCUGGAGUCCAAAUGCAGAGGUUGGGAGCAGGAAGUAGUCAGGCAAGGAAUGUGCAGCUGCUACCAGAGAGAAGCGUUGCUCACUUUGCCAUUUUGCCAAAAUACAGCCAUUCACUGUGAUAGCUUAAGAGUAGGUCUUGAGCCGGGUACAGUGGCUCACACCUGUAAUCCCAGCACUUUGGGAGGCAGAAGCAGGUAGACUGCUUGAACUCAGAAGUUCAAGACCAACCUGGGCAACACGGCGAAACCCCAUGUCUACCAAAAAAGAUACAAAAAUUAGCUGAGCAUGGUGGCACAUGCCGGUAGUCCCAGCUACUCAGGAGGCUUAAGUGGAAGUUAAGUUUGAGCCCAGGGAGGUGAAGGUUGCCAUGAGUCAAGAUCUUGCCACUGUACUCCAGCCUGAGUGACAGAGCCAGACCCUGUCUUGAAAAAAAAAAAAAAAAGAGUGGGUCUUCUCUAUCUGAACAGGUUAAGUGUAUGUGUGUGAGAGAGAGGGUGGAGGAGGAGAGGAGGAAUGGGGAGACGAGGAGUUAUUGUCUCCUCUUAUUCUGUAUAGAAAAUAUAUCAGAUGACGUUCUCCCCAGGAACCUCAGCUGAACUCUGGUGAUGAAGGUAUUAAGGGGAUUAAGGUAUUAAGGGGCAGCGUCAGGUCUUCCCACAGAACCUCCCUGCCCCCAGCUAGGCCCCAAGGACCCAAGAAUCAGCCAAAAGAAUGUAAGGAGAUCUCAUCCUGUUUGCAAUCCCCUUUGUAACUUGCUCCUGGGGAAAACAAGACACAAUGCUAGCUCCUUCCCAGGCCCCUGAGGCAUGAUCACUCGUGUUCCGUGUUCCGGGGAGAGCUUAAGAAAUCACAGUGGCCAGAAGCCCAGCCUCUCUCUCUCCCAGGCAGGACCAAUGGGGCAGUAACCAUCUGGGGAGGGCGGUGGGGGAAUGAAAUGUCAGAGAACAUUUCUCAAUCUGACGGUGUGAGAAAUACUUAUGUAUCUUAGAGUUUGGAAAGCCCUUUUUUCAGUUAAUCCUUAAAACAACCUUGUGAGUUAGGCAUUAGAUAACAUUUUGUCAAACAGUCAUAGGUUUCGUUUUACCUAAAUCCUUCAAACUUCAGUUUCAUUUCCUCUGCAAAGUUAGAGGCUUGUCCUUGGUUAAAUUCCAUGACCACUCUGGGCAGAAAUAAUCCUUUUUAUGCCGAAUUUUACUUGGGCUCGAUGUAUCUGCCCUACACGAGCACAGAAACUCCCUGCCCUGCUGCAGGGCCCUCCUUGGCAUCCUUCCUCACCGCCCCUCUGUCUCCUGCCGCCCCUCCAGUGAUCUCAGCGUCUCAUGGCAGCACUCAUCAGCUCUGCCCUCUCUCCUCCCAGUUGUCCCAGGGCUGCUGCUCCCCUCUGGGAUGACACCCUGAUAGGCACCCACCUCCCUUCCAAUGCCAUCUCCUAGCCCAUCUGACCCCACCAGGUGACAGCACAUCUAGCUACCUCCCUGAGCCAACAGGGCAUUCCUCCAAAGGCUGGUCAACCUUCCCUCGUCAGCCUUGGUGACUCACGUCACCUUUGUUUUCCUUUAGGCUCAGUGGAGCAAACAGAUCCAGAAGGUGCAGGGAACCCUGUGGGUUGUUUAUGAGCAGUCAGGGCCAUUAGGAAAAGCUCCUUUGGCCUGUGGCCUACUUCAGACCCAGGGGCCCCCUCAGGACGGGCAUUCUCCCAGUGUCUUCUGCAUGGGGGUGCUGGAGUCCUGUUGGGCUAAAUAGGCUUUGUAGAUUGGCCCUGAAGCCUAGCCAUGAUAUGACAUUAUUCCUGCAGGGGAAAAAACGUGCCCUAAGUUCCCACAUAUGUUCAUCACAGCACUACUCACAAUAGCAAAGACAUGGAAUCAACCCAAUGCCCAUCAAUGGUAGACUGGAUAAAGAAAAUGUGGUACAUAUACACCAUGGAAUACCGUGCAGCCAUAAACAGGAAUGAGGUCAUGUCCUUUGCAGGGACAUAAAUGGAGCUGGAAGCCAUUAUCUUCAGCAAACUAACGUAGGAACAAGAAAACCAAACAUUGCAUGUUCUCACUUACAAGUGGGAGCUGGACAAUGAGAACACAUGGACACAGGGAGGGGAACAUACUUAGUGGGGCCUGUCAGUGGAUGGUGGCGGUGGGGGAGUAUUAGGGAAAAGAGCUAAAGCAUGCUGGGAUUAAUACCUAGGUGAUGGGUUGUUAGGUGCAGUAGACCACCAUGACACACGUUUACCUACAUAAAAACCUGCACAUCUUGCAUACGUACCCUGGAACUUAAAAAACAAACAAAUUAUUUUUUAAAAAAAGAAACAAUAGAGAAUUUUUUAAAAAUGUGCCCUAAGUUCCAAACAACUGGCUUACAAAAGAGCCCUUGUCGUGUGGCCGCAGUGGCUUCCUCAUUACCAAUAUCCCCAACUUCUGGGGGUUAGAUCUUGAGACCCAAGGGUCUCUAAAACGGGUAGGAUUCAGAGCAACAGUUUACUGACCCAUCUUCUCUUGAACCUCCUUUGCCCCAAAGGUGAAGGGUGGAGGCAAGAGAGGGAACUGUUGGGCACUGAUUAUAUUCCAGGUGUUAAAUGCUUAUGUUAAGUAUUUCAUUGAUUCUCACAGCAGCCUGAAAGGUAAGUAUUAUUACCUCCAUUUAGAGCAGAGGAAAAUGAGUCUCAGAAAUGAAGUAACUUGCCCAAGAUUUGUUAGCCAGUCACUGCCCCCCACAGGUCUGCCCACCCCCAAAGCCAUGCUUUUUCCUGCACAUGCCUGGAGGGGGUGGGAUGGGCAUCAUGCCGGGCCCUGAGCUUCCUGAGACCUCUUGUUUCAGGAGAGCCGGAUCUAUGCUGUGGCCACAUCGGGCAUGCGGCUCUCAGAUAUGUCUCCCAGAAGUAAUACUGCAUGCUGCGGUGAGUUCCAAGUGAGGCUUGGAGGCACCAAACACCCAAGGUGGGCAGGGUGGGCAAGCGGGGAGGAGAAGACUCCAAGCAACACCCAGGGCCAGGGUUGGCUGGCCUACCCUGUUCCCCUCCCCAGCAGGUGAAGUUCAGGUGAAAUCACAGCAAGUCCCACCUAGGAGGGAAAGGGAAGUCGUACAGGUUCAGCCCAUCACAGGAAAGUAGCCAGUCACAGAGCUGGAAGGGAUCUGAGAGGGGGCCUCCAGCCCAGCCUCCCACCUGCACAGGCUUCGCUUCUGCAGUGCCAGGGCCGUGGGUGGGAGGAGCCACAAGUGUCCUGAUUUACAUGAACCCCACUCACUGGCUCCUCUCCAGCCAGCCACCAAAUCUCCACAACGAGGGCUGUGGGGUGGUCCCAUAGCCGUAUGAUUUGUAACUCACAUCUGCAACAGUGGAACACUGUGCAAGCCUCAUGGAGGAAAAAAUGGUUAAAGCUUCAAGCCCUCCUGCCCUUGUUUCCCCUGGGUCUUUCUCUGGCCUGGUCUACAAGAAUGUCACUGUGCCUGUCUACACAGCACUGAAGGGGAGAGCUACACAGAUCAGCAACAUGCCCUUUAUGGACGAGUCCUCUGGGUCUGACGAUGACUGCAGCUCUCAGGCGAGUUUCCGAAUCUCGGUCCCCUCCUCUGAGUCCAGGAAGACCAGCGGACUAGGCAGCCCCCGGGCCAUCAAGAGAGGCGUCUCCAUGUCCUCACUGAGCUCCGAGGGUGACUACGCCAUCCCCCCGGACGCCUGCUCACUGGACAGUGACUACUCAGAGCCUGAGCACAAACUGCAGCGCACCUCAUCCUACUCCACCGACGGGCUGGGCCUGGGCGGGGAGUCACUGGAGAAGUCGGGCUACCUGCUGAAAAUGGGGAGCCAGGUGAAGACGUGGAAGAGGCGCUGGUUUGUCCUGAGACAGGGACAGAUUAUGUACUACAAGUCCCCGAGUGAUGUCAUCCGGAAACCUCAAGGCCAAGUGGAUCUGAACUCCCGCUGCCAAAUUGUUCGAGGGGAGGGUUCACAGACGUUUCAGCUCAUCUCUGAGAAGAAAACCUACUACCUGACGGCCGAUUCACCCAGCCUGCUGGAGGAGUGGAUCCGAGUACUCCAGAGCCUGCUGAAGGUGCAGGCCACCGGGCCUCCAGCUCUGCUUCGGGGUGGCACCAAGCCCACCGUGAAGGGCUGGCUGACCAAGGUAAAGCAUGGCCACUCCAAGGUGGUCUGGUGCGCUCUUGUUGGGAAAAUCUUCUACUACUAUCGGAGCCAUGAGGACAAGCGACCCCUGGGCUGCCUGCCUGUGCGGGAUGCGCACAUAGAGGAAGUAGAUCGAUCCUGUGACUCAGACGAGGACUAUGAGGCUGGAGGAACCAGACGGUUGCUUUCCUCCCACUGCACCCUGGUGAUCCACCCCACAGAGCACAGCCCCACCUACCUCCUCAUUGGCACCAAGCAUGAAAAGGAUACGUGGCUCUACCACCUCACAGUGGCUGCAGGUGGCAGCAGUGCCAAGGUGGGCACUGCCUAUGAGCAGCUCAUUGGAAAACUGAUGGAUGGUGAAGGAGAUCCAGAUUCGCCGCUCUGGAGGCACCCCAUGCUGUGCUACAGCAAAGACGGCCUAUACGCCUCCCUCACCACCCUGCCCUCUGAGGCCUUGCAGACGGAGGCCCUCAAGCUCUUCAAGUCCUGCCAGCUCUUCAUCAACGUGCCGGUGGAAGCUGCCUCGGUGGACUACCAUGUGUCCCUGGCCCAGACCGCACUGCAGGUCUGCCUGGUUCACCCCGAGCUGCAGAGUGAGAUCUACUGCCAACUCAUGAAGCAGACCAGCUGCCGCCCACCUCAGAAGUACUCCCUCAUGCAGUGCUGGCAGCUCCUCGCUCUGUGUGCUCCACUUUUCCUGCCUCAGCAUCACUUCCUCUGGUAUGUCAAGCAGCAGCUCCAACGCCAUGCAGAUCCCAGAAGUGAAACUGGCCAGUAUGCCACCUACUGCCAGCGGGCAGUGGAGCGGACCCUGCGGACCGGGGAGCGGGAAGCCAGGCCAUCGCGCAUGGAAGUGGUGUCCAUCCUGCUGCGUAACCCCUUCCACCACUCCUUGCCCUUCAGCAUCCCCGUGCACUUUACCAACGGGACUUACCAUGUGGUUGGUUUUGACGGCUCUUCCACGGUUGAUGAGUUCCUCCAGCGGCUGAACCAGGAGAUAGGCAUGAGAAAGCCAUCCCACUCUGGCUUUGCCCUCUUCACGGACGAUCCCUCGGGCAGGGACCUGGAGCACUGCCUGCAGGGAAGUGUCAAGAUCUGUGAUGCCAUCUCCAAGUGGGAACAAGCCAUGAAGGAGCUGCACCCCGGAAAGUCUGAGGGUGGGACACGCGUCGUGAAGCUGAUGUACAAGAACAGGCUGUACUUUCGCAGUCAAGUCAAAGGGGAGACGGACCGAGAACGGCUGCUCCUUGCCUCUCAAACCAGUAGAGAGAUAGUGGCAGGGAGGUUUCCUAUCAACAAGGAAUUGGCUCUUGAGAUGGCUGCCCUGAUGGCCCAGGUAGAAUAUGGGGACUUGGAGAAGCCUGCCCUGCCAGGCCCUGGAGGCACAUCCCCUGCCAAGGCUCAGCAUCUUCUCCAGCAGGUCCUAGACAGGUUCCACCCCAGGCGCUAUAGACAUGGGGCCCCCGCUGAACAGCUGAGGCACCUGGCAGAUAUGUUGACCACAAAAUGGGCAACAUUGCAAGGAUGCUCCCCUCCUGAGUGCAUCCGCAUCUACCUGACCGUGGCCAGGAAAUGGCCUUUCUUUGGUGCUAAACUUUUUGCUGCUCAGCCUGCCCAGCUGUCUUCCAAGGAGAACGCUCUGGUGUGGAUUGCUGUGAAUGAGGAUGGCGUCAGCAUCCUGGACCACAACACUAUGCAAGUGCACAUCACUUACCCCUACUCUUCAGUGACAACGUUUGGUGGCUGCAGGGAUGACUUCAUGCUUGUGAUUAGAUCUAUCCCAGACAAGAGCUCUGGAAAAAGCCACAUUGAGAAGUUGAUCUUCCGGAUGGCUGCUCCCAAGAUUGCAGAAGCUACCUUCAUCAUGGCCAGCUAUAUGAACCAUUGCACUACAACUGUGAACCCCCCCACCAACCCACCCGGAGCCUGCCAGCUGUGGGAACUGGAUGGACGACAGUUCUUUUCUUCUGUUUCCUGUGCUACCAAGGGGCCAACGUUGCUGUGAAUAUUUCUCCUACCCGAUUCCCCAACACCACUAGUGCCUCUGGAUUUAGAGAUAUAUAUCCUAGGGUAUGAUACUACUGUGACGGGUCUAACAGCCCCCGGCUACUCUUGUUCUGUGAAAUGUGUAUUUUAGUCUCUGUGAAGCCUUUACUCUCUAGGUGCCUUAUAAUGUUUCAGGGCUCAACUUUUUAAAAUCCAGACCCAGUGUUAAAACCAUUUAUUCCUUUUUUCAUAAGAAUAAUGACUCCAGAUGCUACCUGAUUCUAGACAUAGACAGGGAUGAUCCACUGUUACUGAGGGCAUCAGUGCUAUAAGUUAAGGCUUUCUGCACUGGUACUCUCAAGGAAGCUAAUUUUCUUUCUGGGGGGGGCGGGGGACACAGUGUCACUAUGUCACCCAGUCCACAGGGUUCAAGCAAUUCUCCUGCCUCAGCCUUCGGAGUGGCUGGGAUUACAGGUGUGCGCCACCAUGCCCGGCUAAUUUUUGUAUUUUUAGUAGAGACGGGGUUUCACCAUGUUGGCCAGGCUGGUCUCGAACUCCUGACCUCAGGUGAUCUGCCCACUUUGGCCUCCCAAAGUGCUGGGAUUACAGGCAUGAGCCAUCGCCCAGCCCAGAAGCUAAUUUUUUAAUAUUGUAUAUGGUCUUAUUUAUACUUGAAGUUUUGUGAACGUCGCUAAACAGGAUAGGACUAAAAUUUCCAAUUCUCCUACACUCUGUCAGAAGCCUAGAACUCACUAAACUGGGCUGCCUUUCCCAAAUGGGAAAGGUGCUGACAGAGUUGGAGAAAAAAGAAUAGACUCAUUUUUCCCCAUUAUUGGUAUGUAGGCAUUGGUACAGCCCCUUCUGGGGCAGUCUUUGCAGGAUAACAUGCUAUACCUGCUAAGAUUCAAGCUGUUUUCCUCACACUGGACUUUAGGCCAAACCCAGUACCACGCAAUGUGCAAGCAAGGGCAGGAGGUAGGUCCAAUCUGACCCCUCCCUGUCUCAUUUUAAUGACUGGACAGCGCUCGGUGAAGGCUGUGUUCACUGUAGUGGGCCAUCAUUUGUUUCCUUCUUCUUGUAAAAGACCAAGCAAAUGCACUCUGCUUUUUGCUGCUGUAAGACCACCAAAAAUGAGUCAGAAACACAGAAGACUAUUUCAGGCAUGUGGGCCUGGAUAUGCUCCUUGAGACUUCUGGCAAACUUCUGCUGGGAAUUAGUUUGAGGGUGAGGGUACAUAUGUGACAUUUGCCCUAGCCUAAGAGUAGCAGGUAAAAAAAAGUUUCUUUCAUCUUUUGCCUUACUGAUAAUACCAUAAUCCCCCUCAAUUCAGACCUUCUGAUUGAGUGCAGAGGAGACUAGACAGUCUCCUCUAGACAGGUUGUAGACACACCCUCCCCUAACAAAAACAAAACGAAAGAGUUCAUACUCUGAUUUUCCAACAUCUAGGAAACUGAGUUUUAUUUCCUAGCUCUAAGGCAGCCUUACUAUAUGUCAGUAAAGUGCUGAAAACUGUAUAUUUAGCAGUAGCACCCAAAACCAAGCCUUUAACCCCAACAAUGUGUGUAUCUUUUGCACAGCAAAAACUGCGAGGCCAGAACUAGUUUAUCUGAACACCUCAGCUGCUGUAAGCUUCUCCUCUCUCACCCCGUAAACUGACAAGCAUGAUGAAAAAAGAAGCACAUCCAAGUUUCUGCCUCUUUUAAAUGUACUUGACUUUGCAAGGCAAGUAGUUUUACAGCCAUUUCUGUUCACACUUUUCACCCCACAACUUGGGGAUCUAGCUGAGACAUUUCUACCUCGAACAAGUCACAUGUACCACAGGUUCCUGAAUAAUUCCUGCAGGGCUGGUGACAGACAUAACAGCUCUGGUUUUAUAAUAUCUUGGGUAUCUCUAAGGCCAAUAAGGAUAACAUUAUCUACCCAGAGAGUUUAGAAGAAAAGUAGGAGUCCAAAGGAAGAGUAAACAAGAAUGGAGCUGUGUUCACACUGAAUUUGGGGUCAAUCUAUUUCCCCCACCCUCUCUCCUCCCCAACCCUUCAGGAACCCUUUAGUUUAUUAAUCUUAUACAGAAGAAACUAACUUAGAAACAAAGGAUUCAAUAUUUGCUUAUUUAUUCUUUGUUAACAUGAGAGUCCCAUGUCUGAAAACCAAAGUCCAAUUUCUGUCUGGCCUUUUGUCUCAUCCUUCUUGGCAAAAGUAGCUUUUGAACUGAUAUAAAAAAAAAUGCUGAGUAACAGAAAAGUAUUAAUGUGCUUGACACCAUGACUGAAAUACUAUGAUCUUGUUUGUCAAUAAAAAGCAGCUAUCUGUGAACCAGGUAACUGUGUGUUUUGGAAGAUCUGUUUAUUAACAGUAAAUAAAUAAGCCCUGUACAGAACACAGGCACUAGGUUGACA